CAUUUCAGCCCUGACACCAAGGCAGGAGGCUAGGAGGUCUACAAAUAGCGACUGGGUAGCUGGUGUGAACACAGGGGGUACUGGGGGGGCUUAGCCCCCAAGGAAGAGGACCAGUUUUUCCCCAGCACCACCAUCAAGGCCUCGAGGCUCCCAGCUCCCUCUACAGCCUGUGGACUGACUUAGGGAAUCCCGAACCCUCCCCUUUGAGGACCACCCUACUGCAAGGGACAGAAAGGGAGAGAAGAAUGAAAGGGAUUAGAUUUCAUAGUGGGGUCCAACCUCUUGCAGGAUGACAGAAAAGGAGGUGCUGGAGUCCCCUAAGCCCUCCUUCCCAGCAGAGACUCGGCAAAGUGGGCUACAGCGGCUAAAGCAGUUACUCAGGAAGGGUUCUACAGGGACAAAGGAGAUGGAACUUCCCCCAGAGCCCCAGGCCAAUGGGGAGGCAGUGGGAGCUGGGGGUGGGCCCAUCUACUACAUCUAUGAGGAAGAGGAAGAGGAAGAAGAGGAGGAGGAGGAGCCACCCCCAGAACCUCCUAAGCUGGUCAACGAUAAGCCCCACAAAUUCAAAGAUCACUUCUUCAAGAAGCCAAAGUUCUGUGAUGUCUGUGCCCGGAUGAUUGUUCUCAACAACAAGUUUGGGCUUCGCUGUAAGAACUGCAAAACCAACAUCCAUGAACACUGUCAGUCCUAUGUGGAAAUGCAGAGAUGCUUCGGCAAGAUCCCACCUGGUUUCCAUCGGGCCUAUAGUUCCCCACUCUACAGCAACCAGCAGUACGCUUGUGUCAAAGAUCUCUCUGCUGCCAAUCGCAAUGAUCCUGUGUUUGAAACCCUGCGCACUGGGGUGAUCAUGGCAAACAAGGAACGGAAGAAGGGACAGGCAGAUAAGAAAAAUCCUGUAGCAGCCAUGAUGGAGGAGGAGCCAGAGUCGGCCAGACCAGAGGAAGGCAAACCCCAGGAUGGAAACCCUGAAGGGGAUAAGAAGGCUGAGAAGAAGACACCUGAUGACAAGCACAAGCAGCCUGGCUUCCAGCAGUCUCAUUACUUUGUGGCUCUCUAUCGGUUCAAAGCCCUGGAGAAGGACGAUCUGGAUUUCCCGCCAGGAGAGAAGAUCACAGUCAUUGAUGACUCCAAUGAAGAAUGGUGGCGGGGGAAAAUCGGGGAGAAGGUCGGAUUUUUCCCUCCAAACUUCAUCAUUCGGGUCCGGGCUGGAGAACGUGUGCACCGCGUGACGAGAUCCUUCGUGGGGAACCGCGAGAUAGGGCAGAUCACUCUCAAGAAGGACCAGAUCGUGGUGCAGAAAGGAGACGAAGCGGGCGGCUACGUCAAGGUCUACACCGGCCGCAAGGUGGGGCUGUUUCCCACCGACUUUCUAGAGGAAAUUUAGGCGUGCGGGCGCCUGCAAGCGGGAGACACCCACACCCCAUUCUGGGCGGGCCCAGUGGAGUUUGGGGAGGGGGGCGAAAGCAACGGGACUGCUGGGAGAGGAGGGGUAGGAAGGCCCGCCUGAGCGCGACGGGGCUUCCGGGAAGGGACUGGUUCUCGCCCCCUUCCCCAGCCUGGGGCCUCGGAUACCUGCUGCCCAGAGCAGCCCGGACCCGAAACCUUUCAGGCCCCGCUUGCAAGAGCUGGAAAAAAACGCGUAUCUACUAGGAGGAGCCAGGGACUGGGGCGGGGGGCGGGGGCGAGGGAGGGCGAACUGUCGAAUGUUGCGAAUUUAUUAAACUUUUGACAAAACUUA